AGGCGAACGAACGGGCGGUGUAGUGCAGGUCCGCCAUGGCUGAGGCGUCACGGUGGCACCGAGGCGGGGCUUCGAAACAUAAGUUGCAUUACAGAAAGGAAGUAGAAAUUACAACCACACUUCAGGAAUUGUUACUCUACUUUAUUUUUUUAAUAAACCUAUGUAUAUUGACUUUUGGGAUGGUAAACCCACAUAUGUAUUACUUAAACAAGGUUAUGUCAUCUCUAUUUUUGGACACUUCUGUGCCUGGUGAAGAAAGAACCAACUUUAAGUCCAUUCGCAGCAUAACUGAUUUUUGGAAGUUUAUGGAAGGACCCCUUUUGGAAGGUCUGUACUGGGAUUCAUGGUACAAUAACCAGCAGCUGUAUAAUUUAAAGAACAGCAGUCGCAUCUACUAUGAAAAUAUACUUCUAGGAGUUCCCAGAGUUCGUCAACUAAAAGUCCGCAACAACACAUGCAAAGUCUAUUCAUCUUUUCAGUCUUUGAUGAGUGAAUGUUAUGGCAAAUAUACUUCUGCAAAUGAAGACCUCUCUAAUUUUGGCCUUCAAAUUAAUACUGAAUGGAGAUAUUCUACUUCUAAUACCAACUCCCCUUGGCACUGGGGAUUUCUUGGUGUUUACCGAAAUGGGGGAUACAUUUUCACUUUAUCAAAAUCGAAAUCUGAAACCAAAAACAAGUUCAUUGACCUUCGACUGAACAGCUGGAUCACAAGAGGGACUAGAGUUAUUUUUAUUGAUUUUUCCUUAUAUAAUGCUAAUGUAAAUCUAUUUUGUAUUAUCAGAUUGGUGGCAGAAUUCCCUGCAACUGGAGGAAUACUUACUUCAUGGCAGUUUUACUCUGUGAAGCUCCUCAGAUAUGUUAGCUACUAUGACUAUUUUAUUGCUUCCUGUGAAAUCACAUUCUGUAUUUUUCUUUUUGUCUUCACAACACAAGAAGUCAAAAAAAUAAAAGAAUUUAAGUCUGCCUAUUUCAAAAGUAUUUGGAACUGGCUAGAAUUGCUACUUUUGCUGUUGUGUUUUGUGGCUGUUUCCUUCAACACAUACUAUAAUGUACAAAUUUUUCUCUUACUUGGACAGCUGUUGAAAAGUACUGAAAAAUAUUCAGAUUUCUAUUUUCUUGCAUGCUGGCACAUUUAUUACAAUAAUAUAAUUGCUAUUACCAUCUUUUUUGCAUGGAUAAAGAAUAUGUUCUUGGCAAUUAUUAAUGAUACCUAUUCUGAAGUGAAAGCUGACUAUUCAAUAGGCAGAAGGCUAGAUUUUGAACUUGGCAAAAUGAUUAAACAGAGUUACAAAAAUGUUCUCGAGAAAUUCAGACUGAAGAAAGCUCAAAAAGAUGAAGACAAGAAAACCAAAGGCAGCGGAGAUUUGGCUGAACAAGCCAGAAGAGAAGGCUUUGACGAAAAUGAGAUUCAAAACGCAGAGCAGAUGAAAAAAUGGAAAGAGAGGCUUGAGAAAAAGUAUUAUUCUAUGGAAAUUCAAGAUGACUACCAGCCUGUCACUCAAGAAGAAUUUCGAGAACUUUUUUUAUAUGCUGUGGAGCUGGAGAAGGAAUUACACUACAUCAAUUUGAAGCUAAAUCAAGUGGUGAGAAAGGUUUCAGCUCUAUAGUAUUGAGACAAGUGGAGUCAUUCUGUAAGAAAAAGGCAACAGAAGAAUUCAGUAUGAAGAUUUUCCUCCAAUUUUCUUCAGUAAUGAGAAACAAAAAGUUGGUAAUAACAAAAAGCUUGCAUUUCCAAAGUUCUUGAAGUUGAAAGGAUAAAAUUCCAGUCUUUUGCUAAAAGGAUGUAUCUGUAGUACAAAACAAUGAAGUAAACCAUAUGUUUGCUAAAGGUGGAGAGGACAGUCUGUGGUUAAUAUGGAACAUCACUUACGCUCCCUUGAGAGGGCCUACUUACUCUCCCAUCAUUUGUUUUGUUUAGUGGCACCACAACCAAGUACAAAAUGAGAUUCUCUGAGUGCCUGACAAAACGAAUUUAAGUACCAGCCAAGUACACACGAUGAUAGCUUCAAGGAAUACAACUGACUUUAUGAUAUGAAUUUUCAAGGAACGUAUCUUAUAUGGAUUUUGAAGAAUCUUGUUUGCUUAUAAGAACUUCAAGAAGCCUAAGCUUGGCUUUAAUUUUCUUGUACUCUCUGUACUCCUCAAGCACUGGAACACGAUCCUCUUUCUGGGCAUUCCUAGGGGAGAAAAUAAAAUUUGUAAUGUUCUAGAGAUCAUUUGGAAAAAAAGAUCCAAAAGUUGUCUUAAUAUGAGACAUACUGUUACUAAACAUAAGUUCAAAUAAAAAGUUGUUCUGUUAAAAAAAAAAAAAAA